CUAGAAACAUAGUUGAUGUUCUUACCCUUAUCAUAUAAGGAUAAGAUUAUCCUUAUCAUCCUUAUCAUCAUGAUAAGGAAAACAGCUAGGAAGUUUAACCAUAGGUCAAAUUCUCAUGCAUAGGGAGAAAGGGUUCUGCUAACACUUUUCCUAUACUGACCCUUGUGGAAAUAACUUCUAACUGAAUGAGCUCAUUCAUUGAUUGUGCUAGCCAACCUUAUCACAUCUUAAUUAUAGCACUUCCUCCUACAGAGAACCCAACAAUUUGGUAUAGUACAUUCUAGAUAGAGUUUGUUACUAUCUAAUUCUGGGAUUCCUGCUCUUUUGGCCACAUUUAUCUGUUAUGGCUUACUCUAUAUCAUUUAUUCUAUUUAAAUGUGAUGUUAGUAAUAUUUCAACUUCACCACUUUAAUGCAGCCAUCUAUGGAUAAGUAAUUGGAAAUCUGUGCUAUAAUUUUCCUUUUAGUCAUAGUCUUCCUGGCUCAUUCUGUUUGCCUGCUUACCUGAUGUGGGCAUGCCUCUAUCAGUGCCUGUUAGUUUUGAAUAAAAAGCUUCUGUAAGCACCUGGGCACCAGGUCAGAGAAUUUCUCCAGGCUAGGCUUCCUGUCAUCUGUCUUAAAGGGCCUCAUGAAUGUAUUCCCCUCUUCUGGACCUGAUUAUUAUUAAAUCUUAGCUCCUUUUUCUUGUCUGUUUCUAUUUGGACUUGGCAGUAGGACUUUGUGCUGUACCUUGAUGCUACUUUGGUAACAUCUGUGGCUGCAUCCAGGAUUGCACCUUGGUUUCAUUCAGCUGCUAGAGAAGAUAAGAGAUGCCAUACUCUUACAUUCACCUAUGGGCCUCCAUAAUAUCAUUUGCCAGGGAUAUUUUGCCAUUUCCCAUCUGAGCAAGUACAGAGAAAUCCAGCAAUGAGAUGCCUAGCUGUUUGGCUCACAAAACUACAACUAAUGCAUUACUGUGUAUCUCAUUCCAGGGUACCUGGAUUGACAGUUAAAUGCCUAAGAGAAAAUAGCCACAUAUGAUCUAAACAUAAACCCAGAUUUAUAAAGGAAACACCUACAAGGGCUGACUUAAUUUUUUCUAAGGAAAACCAGAACAUAGCAAAUGGUUAUGGCACAAAUCUAUGUAUGUAGAUAGAGAAGGCAAAGCAAAGGGCAUCAGAAAGAAUGGGAUUAAUUGAGAAAGGUUUUCUCAAGGAGGUAUUGGGUCUUUGAACUUGAUCUAUUAGAUCACUGUAAAUCGCUAUAGGUGAAUCACUGAGGUUGAAAGAGUGGCAUUGGCAUGGCCAAUUGGUGAAACUUGUUGUGGCAGCAACAGAUUAGAGGGGAGAGAGAAAUUGGAUUCUGGUCAUCCAUGAAUAUGUGGCUAGGAGGUGGGUGGGUAGGAGUGAGGAAUUAGGAUUUCCACCAUAUUCUGGCAUUUUUAUGAAGAAAAACUUUACCGUAAAACAUUGACAGAAACAUUGCUGGACUCAAGCUCUCUGGUUUGGAUUCUAAGUUUUUGGAGCCUGCUGUGACUCUUCCCUCUCGCCCUCCUGCUCUUGGAGGAGUGGACUCCCAGCAUCACCUAGGCUUGCUGUAAUUAGGCAUUUCUAAGGAGAACAGGAUACUAAUGAAGAAAUAGUAAUGUAAUCCUUGGAAGAUUUGCAUCUCAGUAAAAUCAGGUGGCCCUUGAUCAUGAAUGGCUCAUUUGCCAUGCUGGGAAAAAUUAAAAAGGAGAUGUCCUUCCUGGCUGGAUACUGGUGUCUGCUUAUACAUUUUGGUAUUUCUUCUGCCUCCACUAUCAGCACCACAACUGCUGAAUCCUCAAUGAGUAAAGAUGCUUCGGUUAUUCUAUUUCUCUGCUAUUAUUGCCUCAGUUAUUUUAAAUUUUGUAGGAAUCAUUAUGAAUCUGUUUAUUACAGUGGUCAAUUGCAAAACUUGGGUCAAAAGCCAUAGAAUCUCCUCUUCUGAUAGGAUUCUGUUCAGCCUGGGCAUCACCAGGUUUCUUAUGCUGGGACUAUUUCUGGUGAACACCAUCUACUUCGUCUCUUCAAAUACGGAAAGGUCAGUCUACCUGUCUGCUUUUUUUGUGUUGUGUUUCAUGUUUUUGGACUCGAGCAGUGUCUGGUUUGUGACCUUGCUCAAUAUCUUGUACUGUGUGAAGAUUACUAACUUCCAACACUCAGUGUUUCUCCUGCUGAAGCGGAAUAUCUCCCCAAAGAUCCCCAGGCUGCUGCUGGCCUGUGUGCUGAUUUCUGCUUUCACCACUUGCCUGUACAUCACGCUUAGCCAGGCAUCACCUUUUCCUGAACUUGUGACUACGAGAAAUAACACAUCAUUUAAUAUCAGUGAGGGCAUCUUGUCUUUAGUGGUUUCUUUGGUCUUGAGCUCAUCUCUCCAGUUCAUCAUUAAUGUGACUUCUGCUUCCUUGCUAAUACACUCCUUGAGGAGACAUAUACAGAAGAUGCAGAAAAAUGCCACUGGUUUCUGGAAUCCCCAGACGGAAGCUCAUGUAGGUGCUAUGAAGCUGAUGGUCUAUUUCCUCAUCCUCUACAUUCCAUAUUCAGUUGCUACCCUGGUCCAGUAUCUCCCCUUUUAUGCAGGGAUGGAUAUGGGGACCAAAUCCAUUUGUCUGAUUUUUGCCACCCUUUACUCUCCAGGACAUUCUGUUCUCAUUAUUAUCACACAUCCUAAACUGAAAACAACAGCAAAGAAGAUUCUUUGUUUCAAAAAAUAGUGGAAUUUCAGUAAACAAUACCUAGAUUUACCUGAUGGUUUGGGGGCAAGAUUUUCUGUUUGCAGUUUUCCCAGUGAUCUGGGGAAUUCAGUUUUGUGAUUGCUGAUCUGACAUCAUAGGCUUUUGAGUGCCUGAAUUUCAGUUCAUUCUGUAAUUUUUUUUUUUUGGUAUGUAAGUAUUUUAAAAUAAGGCACAUUCUGUAAGAAACUUUUUUGAGGCAUUAUUUGUCAUGUAUUUUGCAUGGCCAUUGAAUCCAUGUAUAAUGGAAAUCAUCACAUUGUUUCAUUGUCUAUUGAAGUAUAAUGGGAAAUUCUUCCAAAUUAGAGAACACAUUGGGGUGCACGUGAUGAGUUAGAUAUUUGUGGUUUAGCUGAGGAGCCCUGAGUAAGGGCUCAGCAGUGGAUAGGUGGUCACUGGGAGCCACUGGACUGACCGAAAGCAGAGGAAGGGGGUUCAGUGCAAAGAGAAAAGGAAAAAAGGAAGGUUUCAGAGAGAAAAGAAGGAAAGAGAAAGGUGAAGAGAAAUAGGCGUACACUGGGCCAGGCGCGGUGGCUCAUGCUUGUAAUCCCAGCUCUUUGGGAGGCCGAGGCAGGUGAAUCGUGAGGUCAGGAGAUCGAGACCAUCCUGGCUAACACGGUGAAACCCUGUCUCUACUAAAAAUACAAAAAAAUUAGCUGGGCGUGGUGGCGGGCACCUGUAGUCCCAGCUACUCGGGAGGCUGAGGCAGGAGAAUGGCUUCAACCCAGGAGGCGGAGCUUGCAGUGAGAUGAGAUCGCGCCACUGCACUCCAGUCUGGGCGACAGAGCAAGACUCUGUCUCAAAAAAAGAAAUAGACGUACACUCUGGGACAAGACAGAAAAAGUAUCCUCACACUUGCUGGGUAAUAGUAACUGUGCUAUUCCUAGCAAGAAACCCUAAGGUUUCUAGGCUUGUUCUGGAAAAGAGGAUAUUGCCAGAGUUGGUAAGUAGAGGAAAGUGAUUAGUAUUUAAGAAACUGAAUCAAGAAUGGUUCCAAAAAUCUUAAAAUCCAGGGAAACCAGCUUAAGGUCAAAGGCAAGUGCUAGAUAAUGAAAUUAACACCAUAUGAGUACAAAUUUACAAAAUACUGUACUUCACCAUAGGCUAUGGAACUCAGUGGAAAGCCAAAAAAGCACUGGACAGGUGGUGGGAGUGCUUGACUUGUGGUGAAUUUAUUUCAUCUGCUUAUACAUUUGUACACAGCACAGUUCUUCUCCAGAAUGUUGUUUCUGUGGCUGGGACCAUUGGACUGUGGCUCCAAAAGAACAACAGUCUGAAGAUGGGAUGUUGACAAGUUUUGGAAUGUCAAUUGGGGAAUCAUAAUUUGUAUUUAUUUAGGUUUUUUUUGGUGUUCAUAAAAUGCUUAUGUAAUAUUUACAUAUGUCAAAUAAAUCUUAAAAUUUUAUAAAUUACAUGACUUUUCUCAUUCUGGCCACCAGAAUCUUGACUGCAAUAUUCAGUAAAAAUUACCCAAGCCAAUAUUUUGUGCUAUGAAACCUGGAGGUAUUCAUCAUGUUAAAUCCUAAGAGAGAUAAAAGGAUUACUGAGAGUGAUUAAAUGCAUACUAUGUCUUAAGAACUCUAAAUGAGUGGCAGAAACCCUCAUUGGUCCCUCAGUAUCUGUUCUUUCUCCUCUCUUCCAUAGUAAUCAAAUCAUUAGCUGUUCAGAAUUUUGGCAGCAAAUUCCAUUAUUGCCAUGUAUGUGAGCAGAAAAGAUGUAUAUAAUUUCUGGGUGGUACUUCGGAGCAGUCCUACCUUCCCUUCUUUAAUCUUUUCUUUGUUACUCCCUCCAUGAGCUGGAAUGCUGACAUCAUGAUUGUCUAUCUUGGACAAUGCAGAUGAGGUGAAUGCUUGGGAUAGUGAAGUAAUUCUCCAUCCUAGAGCUGGCUCCAUGGUUCUUCACACUGUGGACUUGUAACACCAGCUCUGGACUGCUCAAGCCUGAACUCCAGGACUGUUGAUGAGAAAUCAGUGUCUCCAUUCUUUCAGGUGCUGGAGUUUUGGUCUCUGUUACCUUAGUCAAAUAACCUAUGCUAUACCUUAAAUAUACACAAUAAUAUAUAUCUUUAUGAUGAAAUAGUAUGUAUUUACCAUCUUAUUAGUCAAAGAACCUUUUUAUAUGACCUACUAAGUGAAAUUGAAAUAAAACCUGUACAUGUGGUAUAAUACCAUUUUUUUUGGUAAAAAUGUGUACAUAUGAAGAAAAGUCUAAAAGGAAAUAUAUAAAAAUGUAAACAGUAAUUAUUUUAGGUGGGAGGAAUCAAUAAAUUUUUUUGUGUAUUUCAA